AGUCCCAGCCCAAGGGUAGCUGGAGGCGCGCAGGCCGGCUCCGCUCCGGCCCCGGACGAUGCGGCGCGCCCAGGAUGCUGCCGUGCCUCGUAGUGCUGCUGGCGGCGCUCCUCAGCCUCCGUCUUGGCUCAGACGCUCAUGGUAAGGCUCCGGGACGCGGCCCUUCCCUGCCCUGCCCUCUCCGCGCCCGCUCCAUUAAAGUUCUCCAUCCAGUGGAGAGCCCUGGCUGGCUGGCCCUCUGGCAGAGCGGUGCCCGGGUGCUCCCUUACUCUGGCAAACCUGGAUCUCAGGCUCACCUGUUGUGGAAGUGGAAGAGGCUGAAAUUGACAGGAACUGACGGAUUGGGAAGGAUAGAGAAGUAUGCGCAAGGCCAAACCCCCAACCCGCAAACCUCAUCAUCCACCCACUUCUAGAUGAGCCGGACAGAGCUGCCCAGCCCUCCGUCUGUGUGGUUUGAAGCAGAAUUUUUCCACCACAUCCUCCACUGGACACCCAUCCCAAAUCAGUCUGAAAGUACCUGCUAUGAAGUGGCGCUCCUGAGGUAUGGAAUAGAGUCCUGGAACUCCAUCUCCAACUGUAGCCAGACCCUGUCCUAUGACCUUACCGCAGUGACCUUGGACCUGUACCACAGCAAUGGCUACCGGGCCAGAGUGCGGGCUGUGGACGGCAGCCGGCACUCCAACUGGACCGUCACCAACACCCGCUUCUCUGUGGAUGAAGUGACUCUGACAGUUGGCAGUGUGAACCUAGAGAUCCACAAUGGCUUCAUCCUCGGGAAGAUUCAGCUACCCAGGCCCAAGAUGGCCCCCGCAAAUGACACAUAUGAAAGCAUCUUCAGUCACUUCCGAGAGUAUGAGAUUGCCAUUCGCAAGGUGCCGGGAAACUUCACGUUCACACACAAGAAAGUAAAACAUGAAAACUUCAGCCUCCUAACCUCUGGAGAAGUGGGAGAGUUCUGUGUCCAGGUGAAACCAUCUGUCGCUUCCCGAAGUAACAAGGGGAUGUGGUCUAAAGAGGAGUGCAUCUCCCUCACCAGGCAGUAUUUCACCGUGACCAACGUCAUCAUCUUCUUUGCCUUUGUCCUGCUGCUCUCCGGAGCCCUCGCCUACUGCCUGGCCCUCCAGCUGUAUGUGCGGCGCCGAAAGAAGCUACCCAGUGUCCUGCUCUUCAAGAAGCCCAGCCCCUUCAUCUUCAUCAGCCAGCGUCCCUCCCCAGAGACCCAAGACACCAUCCACCCGCUUGAUGAGGAGGCCUUUUUGAAGGUGUCCCCAGAGCUGAAGAACUUGGACCUGCACGGCAGCACAGACAGUGGCUUUGGCAGCACCAAGCCAUCCCUGCAGACUGAAGAGCCCCAGUUCCUCCUCCCUGACCCUCACCCCCAGGCUGACAGAACGCUGGGAAACAGGGAGCCCCCUGUGCUGGGGGACAGCUGCAGUAGUGGCAGCAGCAAUAGCACAGACAGCGGGAUCUGCCUGCAGGAGCCCAGCCUGAGCCCCAGCACAGGGCCCACCUGGGAGCAACAGGUGGGGAGCAACAGCAGGGGCCAGGAUGACAGUGGCAUUGACUUAGUUCAAAACUCUGAGGGCCGGGCUGGGGACACACAGGGUGGCUCGGCCUUGGGCCACCACAGUCCCCCGGAGCCUGAGGUGCCUGGGGAAGAAGACCCAGCUGCUGUGGCAUUCCAGGGUUACCUGAGGCAGACCAGAUGUGCUGAAGAGAAGGCAACCAAGACAGGCUGCCUGGAGGAAGAAUCGCCCUUGACAGAUGGCCUUGGCCCCAAAUUCGGGAGAUGCCUGGUUGAUGAGGCAGGCUUGCAUCCACCAGCCCUGGCCAAGGGCUAUUUGAAACAGGAUCCUCUAGAAAUGACUCUGGCUUCCUCAGGGGCCCCAACGGGACAGUGGAACCAGCCCACUGAGGAAUGGUCACUCCUGGCCUUGAGCAGCUGCAGUGACCUGGGAAUAUCUGACUGGAGCUUUGCCCAUGACCUUGCCCCUCUAGGCUGUGUGGCAGCCCCAGGUGGUCUCCUGGGCAGCUUUAACUCAGACCUGGUCACCCUGCCCCUCAUCUCUAGCCUGCAGUCAAGUGAGUGACUCGGGCUGAGAGGCUGCUUUUGAUUUUAGCCAUGCCUGCUCCUCUGCCUGGACCAGGAGGAGGGCCCCUGGGGCAGAAGUUAGGCACGAGGCAGUCUGGGCACUUUUCUGCAAGUCCACUGGGGCUGGCCCCAGCCAGGCCCUGCAGGGCUGGUCAGGGUGUCUGGGGCAGGAGGAGGCCAACUCACUGAACUAGUGCAGGGUAUGUGGGUGGCACUGACCUGUUCUGUUGACUGGGGCCCUGCAGACUCUGGCAGAGCUGAGAAGGGCAGGGACCUUCUCCCUCCUAGGAACUCUUUCCUGUAUCAUAAAGGAUUAUUUGCUCAGGGGAACCAUGGGGCUUUCUGGAGUUGUGGUGAGGCCACCAGGCUGAAGUCAGCUCAGACCCAGACCUCCCUGCUUAGGCCACUCGAGCAUCAGAGCUUCCAGCAGGAGGAAGGGCUGUAGGAAUGGAAGCUUCAGGGCCUUGCUGCUGGGGUCAUUUUUAGGGGAAAAAGGAGGAUAUGAUGGUCACAUGGGGAACCUCCCCUCAUCGGGCCUCUGGGGCAGGAAGCUUGUCACUGGAAGAUCUUAAGGUAUAUAUUUUCUGGACACUCAAACACAUCAUAAUGGAUUCACUGAGGGGAGACAAAGGGAGCCGAGACCCUGGAUGGGGCUUCCAGCUCAGAACCCAUCCCUCUGGUGGGUACCUCUGGCACCCAUCUGCAAAUAUCUCCCUCUCUCCAACAAAUGGAGUAGCAUCCCCCUGGGGCACUUGCUGAGGCCAAGCCACUCACAUCCUCACUUUGCUGCCCCACCAUCUUGCUGACAACUUCCAGAGAAGCCAUGGUUUUUUGUAUUGGUCAUAACUCAGCCCUUUGGGCGGCCUCUGGGCUUGGGCACCAGCUCAUGCCAGCCCCAGAGGGUCAGGGUUGGAGGCCUGUGCUUGUGUUUGCUGCUAAUGUCCAGCUACAGACCCAGAGGAUAAGCCACUGGGCACUGGGCUGGGGUCCCUGCCUUGUUGGUGUUCAGCUGUGUGAUUUUGGACUAGCCACUUGUCAGAGGGCCUCAAUCUCCCAUCUGUGAAAUAAGGACUCCACCUUUAGGGGACCCUCCAUGUUUGCUGGGUAUUAGCCAAGCUGGUCCUGGGAGAAUGCAGAUACUGUCCGUGGACUACCAAGCUGGCUUGUUUCUUAUGCCAGAGGCUAACAGAUCCAAUGGGAGUCCAUGGUGUCAUGCCAAGACAGUAUCAGACACAGCCCCAGAAGGGGGCAUUAUGGGCCCUGCCUCCCCAUAGGCCAUUUGGACUCUGCCUUCAAACAAAGGCAGUUCAGUCCACAGGCAUGGAAGCUGUGAGGGGACAGGCCUGUGCGUGCCAUCCAGAGUCAUCUCAGCCCUGCCUUUCUCUGGAGCAUUCUGAAAACAGAUAUUCUGGCCCAGGGAAUCCAGCCAUGACCCCCACCCCUCUGCCAAAGUACUCUUAGGUGCCAGUCUGGUAACUGAACUCCCUCUGGAGGCAGGCUUGAGGGAGGAUUCCUCAGGGUUCCCUUGAAAGCUUUAUUUAUUUAUUUUGUUCAUUUAUUUAUUGGAGAGGCAGCAUUGCACAGUGAAAGAAUUCUGGAUAUCUCAGGAGCCCCGAAAUUCUAGCUCUGACUUUGCUGUUUCCAGUGGUAUGACCUUGGAGAAGUCACUUAUCCUCUUGGAGCCUCAGUUUCCUCAUCUGCAGAAUAAUGACUGACUUGUCUAAUUCGUAGGGAUGUGAGGUUCUGCUGAGGAAAUGGGUAUGAAUGUGCCUUGAACACAAAGCUCUGUCAAUAAGUGAUACAUGUUUUUUAUUCCAAUAAAUUGUCAAGACCACAGGAAUCGUGUGAAACUAGUCAGAUUGCUGAUGGCACAUUGGCUCAUGGAGGACUCGGUUGUUGAUAAUGAGGAGGGUAAUAAUGUGUGGGAUGUGUGAUGUCACUUUAAGGAAACAGGGCUGAGGACUCAGGCUUAAAUCUGACAGACCCAGGGAGUCCUCAUGCUACCUGUAUUGUGACCUUGGGCCCAUUACUUAUCCUCUCCAAGUUUUAAUUUCCCCACCUGUCACGUGGAGUUGACAACUCCCCAUGAGGAUGUUGUGAGGUGUAAAUGAAAUUGCACAUAAAAAGUUUAACAUGGUGCCAGGCAUGUGGUACUAUGUGCCACUAGCUGUCAUUGGCUGUUGAGUCUGUAAAGAAAAAUGGACAGCUUUUCUUGGAAACAAGUGAAAAUGAAAGCGAUAAGGAGUGUGCAGCGGGACUCUUUCAGAAGACAGAAAAGGAAGAGGUGGAAAGCACAAUGCAACGUUUUGGAUGUGAGUUCUGACAAUGUGGAGAGAAGAACCUGGAAACCCCUCCUUUCCAGGAAGACAGCAAACUGGGCCUCCCUGGAGCUCUGUUCCCAGAGCCCUGUCCCUGGCUCCCCUUGCCCAGGAGGCAUGUCCCAGUGGUGGUUCUCCUAAGUGCGGAAGCCAUCUGCACUCUAUUCUAGAAGCAGCCUGCUCCCUCCAUGAAAAACCCCAUGUGGGUUUGAAUUUCUCCCCAUGCUCAGCCCAGUGGGUAGAACAAACCCAGGCCCGCGGCCUGAGCUUCCUGGGUGUGCUUUUCUCUUCGUCCUACCUGAAUCCCCUAGAAGGUGACUGGGGACACCUCACCUCUUUUCCCCUGUGUCAUCUCCAAUCUUGCCUCACCCAGUUCAUUCUGAGAAAAUAACUAGUUCUGAGGAAGUGCUGAUCCUAUCAUCUUCAGAGAACUUGACUAAUAUCACGCCAUUUCAGACCUGCUCAGGCUUUUGCCCUAGAGCCCUCCUUGUCAAUAUUGGAAAGAAAAGUAGUGUUGGUCACUUUCUCCUGGAAAUGAGGUGUUAGCGAUGGCUUAUUCCCCAUGGAAAAGGCCCCUAAGGUCUAAAUAUAAAGAUUCAGAGAGUAAAAGGAAUUACAUUCAAGGAACUGCAGCCAGUUUGGUUGGAUACGACAGAUCAAAGAGCAGCUUGCAGGACAGAAGGAAGUCAGAAGACACAGCCCUUGGUGCAGGCCCUGCCUGCUCCGUUUCUGUGGAAUGAGUAGGAGUUUGCGCUGGUUCAUCUCUGCUUUGAGGCUGCUCUGUAACCACUCACCACAGACAGGCCCUUGGGAGAAACUGAGCGAGUCCUUCCAAGCAGCCGGGGCUGAUGAGACACUUGCAGAUUUCUUGGGAAUUUGGAUUACAGCCCCCAACAGAAGGCCCCAGCUGUUCUUCAACUGAGCAAUCUCCUUCAAGGGCUUUUCCAAGCUGAGGAAUGCGUAAUGCUGUCUUUGUGUGAGCUAAUGGAACUUCCUCUUAGUACAGAGAGGGGGUAAAUGGGCCACCAUUGAGUGAAGAGGAAAUUCAAUAAACUGUGUUUUCCCAACUUUGUAAA